GUGAACCCGGAAGGUGGCGCGGCCACCAGUAACAUGAUCUCUAGACUGGGACGGUGGGGUUCCUGCCGGCUGUAUUCGGGCCUUGGACUGGACUGAGAAGCUACGGUGGAGACCAUCCAUGGAAAAGAACCCCCCUGAUGAUACGGGCCCCGUGCACGUGCCUUUGGGGCAUAUUGUGGCCAAUGAGAAAUGGCGCGGGUCACAGCUGGCGCAGGAGAUGCAAGGGAAAAUUAAGCUCAUUUUCGAGGAUGGCUUGACACCAGACUUUUAUCUGUCGAACAGAUGCUGCAUUCUUUAUGUCACCGAAGCUGAUUUGGUGGCAGGAAAUGGCUACAGAAAGAGGCUUGUUCGGGUUAGAAAUUCCAAUAAUCUUAAAGGAAUUGUAGUCGUUGAAAAAACCCGGAUGAGUGAACAAUACUUCCCAGCCCUACAGAAGUUUACUGUGCUGGACCUUGGAAUGGUGCUGCUUCCAGUGGCCAGCCAGAUGGAAGCAUCCUGCCUCGUCAUCCAGUUGGUUCAAGAGCAAACCAAAGAGCCCAGUAAGAACCCUCUUCUCGGGAAGAAACGGGCCCUGCUGCUGUCUGAGCCUUCGCUCCUUCGAACCGUGCAGCAGAUCCCAGGAGUUGGAAAAGUUAAAGCUCCCCUUCUCCUCCAGAAGUUUCCAAGCAUCCAGCAACUGAGUAAUGCUUCCAUUGGGGAACUGGAGCAGGUGGUCGGACAAGCAGUGGCACAGCAGAUCCAUGCCUUCUUCACGCAGCCCAGGUGAGGGCUGGCCUCAGGGCCACGGCAUCUUCUCCUGAGACCACAAACACCAGGAUCUUGUUUUCAGCUUUAAAAACCAAGAGAAUGGGCCGGGUGCACUGGCUCACGCCUCUAAUCUCAGCACUUUGGGAGGCCGAAGACAGCGGAUCAUCUGAGGUCAGGAGUUCAAGACCAGCCUGGCCAACAUGGAGAAACCCCUAAAAAUAGGAACAAUUAGCCAGGCAUGGUGACAGGUGCCUGUAAUCCCAGCUACUUGGGAGGCCGAGGCAUGAGAAUCACUUGAACCCGGGAGGCGGAGGUUGCAGUGAGCUGAGAUCGUGCCACUGCACUCCAGCCUGGGCACCAGAGCGAGACUCCGUCUCAAAGAAAACAACAAAAAAAAAAAAAAAAGAAAAAGGAUUUUCUCCAGCAGCAACCAGUGAAAGAUGAGGCGAGGCUUGAAUGGAGCCCGUGGGUCGUCCUGCCUUAGCGUCUGAGUUCAGCUUGUGAAGUUAGUGGGCCGCAGAGGGCACUGCCUUCAUUCUGCUAAGACGAAAAGGGCUGGUGGGAUCUUCGCAAGAGAGUCAGGGACUCACACUCAGCAAAAAGCAUUAGGGCCGAUUUUAAUGUGCGACCUUGACCUGCAUCUGUCAUGGAAAGUGCCUUCUAAAAAGCUUCAGUGGUGGAUGUGACCAUCUGAAGGAAACAAAUGUACAAGGAAGCACUGUGUAUCCUAAGCCCUGGGUUCCCAGAGUUUCACCUGCUGUUCAUCAGGUCUGGCCUUCAUAUACCCGUACUGCGAGGGCUGUUUCCAAUGUAAAUAAAUAACUGCGCAACAGUUCCUUCCUCCUUUCCUUUGUUCCUCCCUCCCCCCGGCCUUUUUUUUUGGCAGAUGUACAGUUUGUUUAUAAUCACUGCAUAUGUCUUCUGCACACAGAAAGUAUGAAGUCUGAAGUUCCCACUUAAAGUUGAAAACUCAACGGCCGGGCAUAGUGGCUCACACCUGUAAUCCCAGCACUUUGGGAGGCCAAGGGGGGUGAAUCACAAGGUCAGGAGAUCCAGACCAUCCUGGCCGACAUGGUGAAGCCCUGUCUCUACUAAAAAUACAAAAAUUAGCUGGGUGUGGUGGCACACACCUGUAAUCCCAACUACUCAGGAGACUGAGGCACGAGAAUCGCUUGAACCCAGGAGGUGGAGGUUGCAAUGGGCCGAGAUUGCACCACUGCACUCCAGCCUGGAUGACAGAGUGAGACUCCAUCUCAAAAAAAAAAAAAAAAAAUUUAAAGUUGAAAACUCAACAUGCAUGAGGCAGAACAGGCUGUGUUUGUAUAUGAAAGGCCCAACAAUGGAAGGAUACAAGAAAAUGAUGGCAGCAGCUGCAUCUAGUGAGGGAAGCAGGGGCUGGGGAUCAAAAGGUACAAAUUGCCCAUUCAAAAAAUAGACACAGGCCAGGCACAGUGGCUCACACCUGUAGUCCCAGCACUUUGGGAGGCUGAGGUGGGAGGAUUGCUUGAGUCCAGGAUUUCGAGAUCAGCCUGGGCAACAUGGCAAGACCCCAUCUCUACAAAAAAA